AGGCUGACAGAGAAAUUUUUCAUUUUCUUUCUUGUUUGACUGUAUGCAAACAUCAAACUAAGAAUGGCAAAAAUGAAUCUCUCUUCCUAUAUAUUAAUACUAACUUUUUCUUUGUUUUCUCAAGGUAUUUUACUUUCAGCAUCCAAGUCCAUAAGAAAUUUAGAUGAUGACAUGGUAUUUAAUACAUUCAGGUUGGGGAAAGGCUUUCAGAAGGAAGACACUGCAGAAAAAUCAGUUAUUGCUCCUUCCCUGGAACAAUAUAAAAAUGAUGAGAGCAGUUUCAUGAACGAAGAGGAAAAUAAAGUUUCAAAGAACACAGGCUCCAAACAUAAUUUCUUAAAUCAUGGUCUGCCACUGAAUCUGGCUAUAAAACCUUAUCUUGCACUAAAAGGAUCUGUAGCUUUCCCAGCUGAGAAUGGAGUUCAGAAUACUGAAUCAACACAAGAAAAGAGAGAAAUUGGGGAUGAAGAAAACUCAGCUAAAUUUCCUAUAGGAAGGAGAGAUUUUGACAUGCUCAGAUGUAUGCUGGGAAGAGUCUACCGACCUUGUUGGCAAGUCUGAUACCUGUUGGUCCACAUCAUCUUUUCAGAAGAAAAUAAAAGCAUUUAAUUGCCAAUGGGAGGAGAAGCCCAUACUGCUACUAUAACUUGUGUAUGUUAAAUGUCUGUUUUAAAAGAAAGUAGUGUUAAGAUGUAUCAGUAACUGAAAUGAUAUGCUUUCUCUGUGCAUUAAACUUUGUGAAAAUUCUGCAUAA